GAGCUGAGAUCACACCACUAUACUCCAGCCUGGGCAACAAAGUGAGACUCCAUCUCAAAAGCAAAAAGCAUUAAUUAUAGGAGCACUGUGAAGAAGAAGAGGUGAGAACGACCCCCUAGGCUGACCAAAGCCCGUGUGCCACCGUAUCCCCAUGCAUUGCUGCAUCCCUGCAGCCAGCACCUGUGUGCAGCCACCAUUGCCACCAUGCCCAAGAGAAAGGCUGAAGGGGAUGCUAAAGAAGAUAAGGCCAAGAUAAAGGACAAACUACAGGGAAGAUCCACAAAGUUGUCUGGAAAGCCUGCUCUGCCAAAGCCACAGCUGAAGCCUAAAAAGGCCCCUACAAAAAAGGGAGAGAAAGUAUCCAAAGGGGAAAAAGGAAGAGCCAACUCUGACAAAGAGGUGAAUAAACCUGCAGAAAAUGGAGAUGCCAGAACGGAGAAGGCACAGAAAGCUGAAGGUGCUGGAGAUGCCAAGUGAAGUGUAUGCAUUUUUGAUAAAUCUGUACUUCUGGUGACUGUACAGUUUGAAAUACUGUUACAUCCCAAUGGAUUAUUCUUGCCUGCUGCACAGAAAAGCCCAUAUGCUGAAACAGCAGUGUUGCAGUAGGGAAAGAGUUCAAUUAUUGCAAGGCAGCUGAGUGGGCAGACAGGAAACAUUUCUCAAAUCCAUCUCCCUGAAAGCUUGGAAGCUAGGGUUUUUAAGGAUAAUUUGGCAGGCAGGGGUUAGGGAAUGAGUGCUGCUGAUUAGUUGAAGAUGUAAUCACAGGUGUGUCCAAAACAGUCUUUAUUUGUUGAGUCAGUCUCUGAGUGGGGAGUCACAGGACUGGUUCAGUUAGUUCCUUGGUAUGAGUCAUGGGUCCAGGUGGACUCAGUUAGUUGCCAGAAUGCAAAAGUCUGAAAAACAUCUCAAAGACCAAUUUCGGGUUCCACGAUAGUAAAUUAUCUAUAGGAGUAACUGAGGAAGUUACAGAUCUUGUGAUCUCUAGCUUCAUCACCUCUGAACUGGAAAGAAUUAUAGAAAAACCAAGCUAGGGAACAACAGCUGGUUAUUGUUUAACUAUGCCCACAUUUUAGCAGAAUUCAGGUCCUCCCCAUAAUCUUAACCUUGUGGCCUUUCAUUAGCCUUACAAAGGCAGUUUAACUCCCCAGAUGGGGUCAGUUUGGAGAGGGACUAUUAUUAUCCUUGCUUCAAAGUUAAACUAUAGGCUGGCUGGGUGGAGUAGUUCAUGUCUGUAAUC